GCUCCGCGCUCGCUCGUUCGCUCGCUCGCUCGCGCUCCCCGGCGCCGGCUGCGGAGGGAGCUGCUCUGCCCGCAGCUGGCGCAGCGCGGGGGCGGCCGCGGGUGGGCGGGUGCCGCGGGCCCGGGCGCCGAGCAUGAGCCGCCGCCGGCGCCGGCCGCGCGCUGCUCGGGGCCCGACUGCGGCGCGAGGGCGGCGCGGGAGCGACGCUGGCCCGGACCGAGGAAACUAUGCCCCAGACGUCCGUUGUCUUCUCCAGCAUCCUUGGGCCCAGCUGUAGCGGACAGGUGCAGCCUGGCAUGGGGGAGCGUGGAGGCGGGGCCGGUGGCGGCUCCGGGGACCUCAUCUUCCAAGAUGGACACCUCAUCUCUGGGUCCCUGGAGGCCCUGAUGGAGCACCUUGUUCCCACGGUGGACUAUUACCCCGAUAGGACGUACAUCUUCACCUUUCUCCUGAGCUCCCGGGUCUUUAUGCCCCCUCAUGACCUGCUGGCCCGCGUGGGGCAGAUCUGCGUGGAGCAGAAGCAGCAGCUGGAAGCCGGGCCUGAAAAGGCCAAGCUGAAGUCUUUCUCAGCCAAGAUCGUGCAGCUCCUGAAGGAGUGGACCGAGGCCUUCCCCUAUGACUUCCAGGAUGAGAAGGCCAUGGCCGAGCUGAAAGCCAUCACACACCGUGUCACCCAGUGUGAUGAGGAGAAUGGCACAGUGAAGAAGGCCAUUGCCCAGAUGACACAGAGCCUGUUGCUGUCCUUGGCUGCCCGGAGCCAGCUCCAGGAACUGCGAGAGAAGCUCCGGCCACCGGCUGUAGACAAGGGGCCCAUCCUCAAGACCAAGCCACCAGCCGCCCAGAAGGACAUCCUGGGCGUGUGCUGCGACCCCCUGGUGCUGGCCCAGCAGCUGACUCACAUUGAGCUGGACAGGGUCAGCAGCAUUUACCCUGAGGACUUGAUGCAGAUCGUCAGCCACAUGGACUCCUUGGACAACCACAGGUGCCGAGGGGACCUGACCAAGACCUACAGCCUGGAGGCCUAUGACAACUGGUUCAACUGCCUGAGCAUGCUGGUGGCCACUGAGGUGUGCCGGGUGGUGAAGAAGAAACACCGGACCCGCAUGUUGGAGUUCUUCAUUGAUGUGGCCCGGGAGUGCUUCAACAUCGGGAACUUCAACUCCAUGAUGGCCAUCAUCUCUGGCAUGAACCUCAGUCCUGUGGCAAGGCUGAAGAAAACUUGGUCCAAGGUCAAGACAGCCAAGUUUGAUGUCUUGGAGCAUCACAUGGACCCGUCCAGCAACUUCUGCAACUACCGUACAGCCCUGCAGGGGGCCACGCAGAGGUCCCAGAUGGCCAACAGCAGCCGUGAAAAGAUCGUCAUCCCUGUGUUCAACCUCUUCGUUAAGGACAUCUACUUCCUGCACAAAAUCCAUACCAACCACCUGCCCAACGGGCACAUUAACUUUAAGAAAUUCUGGGAGAUCUCCAGACAGAUCCAUGAGUUCAUGACAUGGACACAGGUAGAGUGUCCUUUCGAGAAGGACAAGAAGAUUCAGAGUUACCUGCUCACGGCGCCCAUCUACAGCGAGGAAGCUCUCUUCGUCGCCUCCUUUGAAAGUGAGGGUCCCGAGAACCACAUGGAAAAAGACAGCUGGAAGACCCUCAGGACCACCCUUCUGAACAGAGCCUGAGGCGGAUGCAGCCCGCGACGCCAGAGGAAGCACGUGCACUAACUGGGUUUAAAUUUUGACUGAUGUGGGUUGAGAUGAGGAGGCCUCACUGGUUGGGGUCCAUUUUGUAUAUAACUUUUAUGAGAAAAAAAUGGUAAUUAUUUCACGCAUCAACCUUUGGCACUUACAAAGUUUUUUUUGUUUAUUUUAAAUAACAGGGCAGGGCCCUGCUUUGGGGAGGGGGAGGGGAGAGUAUCAUGGGAGAUGGUAUCCAUGAUAACAUCUUAUUCUAAUGAAAUGUAGAUUUUUAUUUUCUACUUUUGAUUAUUAACAUCUUAUGAAAAAAAUAUUUUAAAAAACCCAGCCAAAACCAACGUGAGCCCUGCCUGCUCGGACGCCUUUCCAGCCAGUGUCUCUGACGUCGGGGUUAGUGCCUUAGAGGGUACUGGGGUCUGGUCUUCCUGCUCUGUGGUUUGGGCUGCGGUGAGUCCCACUCCACCUGGGCGCCUGCCCUCAGGAGCCUGGGCUGCGAGGCUCCAUAGGAGGGCUGGUGGCUGGGAGGUCGCGUCCGCACACUUCUGGAAGUGAGCCUUUGAGUACGGGCUGUCCAAAGUUUACAUUUUCAUUUUCCUUUCAGGGAUUUGUGGGGUCAGGGAGGGGCAGGGGGCACCUGGCAGCAUAUUUUCUGUGACAAUGUGUCCAGCAAAUCAUUCUUCAACUACAUUUUAGAAAGGAGGAAAUCUAAAAUAAGGUAAGGGAGGGAAGCAUGGAGUUGUCAGUUUUCUGGGCUGUGACUGAAAGACACACUGAGCUGUGAUGAAGAAAAAUACAUGGCCGACUCCAGGGUGGUGACAUUUAGAGCUAGUCUUGAAACCUAUCAUCUACAGAGGGGAGGGCAGCCAACAGCCCUCUUCCCACCUGGGUAGGCAGCGCCCUAAUUGGAAUUGGAAACAGAAAAUUCGCCAGGCCAUACUGCUGGAGCCCAUUCAGAUAAAACUGCCCAAUACUGAGAGGUGUUUUCUACACCCAGCUAGAGGAGCACACUCCAUUUUCCCAUGUCUGACUUCGUGGUGUGAGCCCUGGGCCCUACUGACCAUGGCGCAGGACAGCUGUCCUUCAGAAAGCACACGGUCAAUCCACGUGGACCGUCUCCCUCGCAGGAACUCCGCAUCCUUGUCCCUCUGCAUUCCCAGUUUCCGCAGGAGCCUUGAUCAAUGGGGAAGCCUGGGUGAGGAUGGGCCAGGUCCCAAUUCCCAAAGCUCCUGGAAGAGCCUGAAGACAUUGGGAAAGGCUGGGCCUGGGGAGGAGGCAGCCCUGGGCCCGCUGCCCAUGCCUCUGGUCCUGGGUGGAGCAGGAAUAGUUCCACUGUAUUGUCACAGUGUGUUUGCACUUUCUGAGGUUCUAGCUAGUACAGAUUGUAUAUUGAUAGUACAUAUUGCUUUGUUUAUGUCUUUGAGAUGAGAAAGGCUUAAAACUUGAGAAUAUAUAUUUGGAAUACAGCCUUAGAACGGUUUCUGUACACACCCACGUGCACUUCACGGGUGAUCAGUUCUAGUACCUACUUGAAACAGUGUCUGUCUGCUACUUUAUUUUCCCAAUUUGAUACAUACCCUGAUUUGAUGUUUUGGUAUUUGAGAUGAACUCUGAGUAUGAAGCUGUACCAUAAUGCAGGACGUCAGUUUUGGUGUGACUGGACAUACUUGCUUCAAUAAAAGAAUACAUCACUCCCC